AUGGGCCCCGCCGCCAGGGGGCGCAGCGCUCCCUUCCCGGCCGUUCCACGGCGGUUCGCGGUUCCCGCUGCCCAGGAGCUGGAGGCGGGCCCGGCGCCUUGGGUGUGCACCCGGGCUGGCGCGAGGCCUGGCCGGCCGGCCGCAAAGCUGAAGCCUGGGGCGCUCGCCGCUCCUCGUGAGCGCUCCUUUCCUUCUCUAUGAUAAACGUGAUUUCCCACGCAUGCUUUGCCCUUGCCUCAUCCGUGAGCUGUGCACCACCGAUUUGGAGGCCCUUGUGUGCUUGUUUACCUACGUCUCCCUAUGUAGCUAUUUUAAACAAGGUGUUUUUACAGAGAUAAAAGUUUUAUUGAUUGCUCAGGUGGUCUUUCUGGAAGAAUUCUGCACGUAAACGCUAACUCGACAAGAGUGCCGGGAGGAACAAGGUUACUCACUAGAGUUGGAAAUGUGCAGUUCAUCUCCUUAAAGUAACUUUUGAAUGGUUGAAUACAAAUAGUAAACAUGCCACAGGGCAGCGUGGCAUAGUGCCAGAAAGCUACGGUUGCAGGAAACUGAGGUUUAAUUUUUAGAAGUCAAUGUCACCUGUAGCAGAGAAGUUCCUUGAAAUCAAAUCAGACAUAUGGCAAUUGUGAAAAGAUUGAACGGAAUAGAAGAUGAACUCAACUGAAUUCACCGAAGAUGUAGAAGAAGUUCUAAAAAGUAUCACUGUGAAAGUGGAGACAGAGGCUGAAGAUGCUGCUCUGGACUGCUCCGUGAAUUCCAGGACUUCUGAGAAGCACUCUGUGGACAGCGUCCUCACUGCCCUGCAGGACUCCAGCAAACGAAAGCAGCUGGUCAGCGAUGGCCUGCUAGACUCUGUCCCCGGCGUGAAGAGGAGGCGGCUGAUCCCCGAGGCUCUCCUAGCAGGCAUGCGGAACCGUGAGAACAGCUCGCCCUGCCAAGGCAAUGGUGAGCAGGCCGGCAGGGGCAGGAGCCUGGGCAAUGUGUGGCCUGGAGAGGAGGAGCCCUGCAACGAUGCCACCACCCCUUCCUACAAGAAGCCUCUGUAUGGCAUCUCGCACAAGAUCAUGGAGAAGAAGAAUCCUCCCUCGGGGGACCUGCUAAACGUGUACGAGCUCUUUGAGAAGGCAAACGCCAGCAACAGCCCCUCGUCACUGCGGCUCCUGAAUGAGCCACAGAAGCGGGACUGUGGCAGCACCGGGGCAGGCACUGACAACGACCCCAACAUCUACUUCCUGAUCCAGAAGAUGUUCUACAUGCUGAACACCCUCACGUCCAACAUGUCCCAGCUGCACAGCAAGGUGGACCUGCUCUCCCUUGAGGUGAGCCGCAUCAAGAAGCAGGUGAGCCCCACUGAGAUGGUGGCCAAAUUCCAGCCGCCCCCUGAGUACCAGCUCACAGCCGCAGAGCUCAAGCAGAUCGUGGACCAGAGCCUGUCAGGGGGGGACCUGGCCUGCCGCUUGCUGGUGCAGCUCUUCCCCGAGCUCUUCAGCGACGUGGACUUCUCCCGGGGCUGCAGUGCCUGUGGCUUUGCGGCCAAGCGCAAGCUGGAGUCGCUGCACCUGCAGCUCAUCCGCAACUAUGUGGAGGUCUACUACCCCUCGGUGAAGGACACGGCUGUGUGGCAGGCCGAGUGCCUGCCCCAGCUGAACGACUUCUUCAGCCGCUUCUGGGCCCAGCGGGAAAUGGAGGACAGCCAGCCCAGCGGCCAGGUCGCCAGCUUCUUUGAGGCAGAGCAGGUGGACCCCGGCCACUUCCUGGACAACAAAGACCAGGAGGAGGCCCUGUCUCUUGACCGGAGCAGCACCAUCGCCUCAGACCACGUGGUGGACACGCAGGACCUCACUGAGUUCCUGGACGAAGCCUCCUCACCAGGCGAGUUUGCCGUCUUCCUCCUCCACCGGCUCUUCCCCGAGCUCUUCGACCACCGCAAGCUGGGUGAACAGUACAGCUGCUACGGGGACGGUGGAAAGCAGGAGCUGGACCCGCAGCGGCUGCAGAUCAUCCGCAACUACACGGAGAUCUACUUCCCUGACAUGCAGGAGGAGGAGGCCUGGCUGCAGCAGUGUGCCCAGCGCAUCAACGACGAGCUCGAGGGCCUGGGGCUGGACGCGGGCAGUGAAGGCGACCCCCCGCGUGAUGACUGCUACGACUCCUCCAGUCUGCCCGACGACAUCUCAGUGGUCAAGGUGGAGGACAGCUUCGAGGGCGAGCGGCCGGGUCGCCGCUCCAAGAAGAUCUGGCUGGUGCCCAUCGACUUCGACAAGUUAGAGAUCCCCCAGCCUGACUUCGAGGUGCCCGGUGCCGACUGCCUGCUCAGCAAGGAGCAGCUACGCAGCAUCUACGAGAGCAGCCUGUCCAUCGGCAACUUCGCCUCGCGCCUGCUGGUGCACCUGUUCCCCGAGCUCUUCACGCACGAGAACCUGCGCAAGCAGUACAACUGCAGCGGCUCCCUGGGCAAGAAGCAGCUGGACCCCUCCCGCAUCAAGCUCAUCCGCCACUACGUGCAGCUGCUCUACCCACGCGCCAAAAACGACCGCGUCUGGACCCUGGAGUUCGUGGGCAAACUGGAUGAGCGCUGCCGGCGCCGGGACACGGAGCAAAGGCGCUCCUACCAGCAGCAGCGCAAGGUCCACGUGCCGGGCCCUGAGUGCAGAGACUUGACCAGCUAUGCAAUCAACCCCGAGAGGUUCCGGGAGGAGUUUGAGGGGCCCCCACUGCCCCCCGAGAGGAGCAGCAAGGACUUUUGCAAGAUCCCCUUGGACGAGCUGGUGGUCCCCUCGCCUGACUUCCCGGUGCCUUCUCCCUACCUGCUGUCUGACAAGGAGGUGCGUGAGAUCGUGCAGCAGAGCCUCUCCGUGGGCAACUUUGCCGCCCGGCUCCUCGUCCGCCUGUUUCCCGAACUCUUCACCGCCGAGAACCUCCGGCUGCAGUACAACCAUUCCGGGGCUUGCAACAAGAAGCAACUGGACCCCACGCGGCUGCGGCUCAUCCGCCACUACGUGGAAGCCGUCUACCCGGUGGAGAAGAUGGAGGAGGUGUGGCACUACGAAUGUAUCCCCAGCAUCGAUGAGAGGUGCCGCCGCCCCAACAGGAAAAAAUGCGACAUCCUCAAGAAAGCAAAGAAAGUGGAGAAGUGAAGGCCCGUGACCUGCCCAGAGAUUCGGGGUCACCAGAGGCUGAGCGAUGGGCACCCUUGGGACUGAGCAAUACUUGGGAGCACGCCUAUGGCAUCCACAGACAGGCACCUUAUGUCCGUGGGGAGUGGCUUACUACAUUUGCACACGUAAACACCCACCCAACCGCAAGAAAGAAGCCUUGAGUUUGGUCUCUUGUACUUACAACUUCUGUCCUAUGUGCCCCGGCGGGGCAGCCUGAGUGUGGGGAGAGCAAGCUGUGAGGGCAGGGACCAGAGGUUAGGGGUCCUCUCUCCCUGGUUGUGCCCUCCCCAGCCCCUCACAGCUUAUAAUGCAAACCCAGCAACUCUCUUGCCCCUCUUCCCAUAUUUUACAUCUUCCAUUUUGACCCAUUUUUUUUUAAUUAAAAAGAAACCCUUAAAAAAAAUCAUUGGGCUCUUUGGGGGCCAUUUUACUUAGAAAAAAAUCUCUUUAAAAGUGCCAUGUUCGUGCACAGUGGCUAAUCAUAGCUUCAGGUGGCAUGGAUACUGAUUUUACUGACCUUGUUUUUUACAUCUGAUUUUGGAAGAGUCAAGAUGCCCCUUGGAUGGCAGUAGAGGGGAUGGAAUAGUGCGAAGUCCUUUACGACCACAUGCAAGUUUUCCCUUCUGCUCUGGUGCCAGGGAAGGCUUCCGUUCAGCUUGGCCUGUCCUUCAGGCGCGUUGGUAGAAUGUUGUGUCACUCUUUAGGCGAGAACACUGGAUGAUGAUGAUAUGAAUGUAGACAGCCGUGGAAACACGUUCGCAGUGUCUCCAUCUGAGCCGUGUCCUUCCGCUGCCCCCAUUCCUUCUCCAUACAUGGUUGCUGGUUGGAGGGAGUGGACAUGUUUCCUUGGAAAACAGUGCAGGGGCUUUUGGCUUCUUGUUAGAUUUAAGGGUGGGCCUCUUUGAGCUCACCAUGAACUGUUUACUUUUCCGUGUGUGUAUUUGUACAAAAUCCAGGUUCCGGGAGCUUUGUGGUGACUUCCCCAGACCUCAGUGUUAGCUACUCCAGGCAGUACUACAUCCUCAUUCCUCAGGGCGGGCCCAGGUCUGGGCCCCUCUUGGGGAUACCAUGCAUUGGAAGGACACAGGCCAUUUUAGAUGGGGUACACAUGUCCCUUCCCAGGGUCCACUCAGAACUUUCCUCUUGGACUCUCUAGAAGGUCCUGCUGUCCUAUACCUGGCCACCCCCUGCCUUGGGGGGCACAUGUCUUCGUUCCCUCCCGACUGGGAAUGUCAGGCUCCUGCAGGCCAGCUGCAUGCUCUCCAGGAGCACCAACUGGGAAAUCCCCUGACAGGUAAAGUCCUUUAAAAUGAUACUUUUACCUACCUAACUCUGGGGGCCAAAUGCUUAAGAGGGAAAGGAAACAGUCGAAUGCAAACAGUGUGUCAUACCAGAGUCCUGGAAAAUUUAUUGAAUCACACAGGGUAGUCAUAGAACCCCUGUGGGAUGGCUUAAUAUUUUGCUACUUUAAAAUGCAGAGAUAACAGAAACAAUCUGGAUUUUCUUCAUUCAGCUGAUAAGAACUUCAGUUCCAGUGGCUGUAUGACAUAAUUUUGCCUGUACCCAGGAGCAUUUUUUAAAAUACAGGAUUUUAAAAGCAAUGUUAAGUUGCUGAUCUAACUAGUAAAUUUGCUCCUAAGUGUCAUUUACAGAUUAUUUCUGUUGAAACUGCAAACAGAUUUAGAAAGGCACAGGGACUGAAUGACUCUCUGUCUUACACAGCUACUCAUGCACACACGCACUGCUUACUAAAAGCUGAAGUGAGAUGAAGGGGGCCUACACGAAUAACAAGUUCAACUUCUUUGUGCCUGGAAAGGAGGGACUGGAGCAGCCAGGAGACUCACUUUCCCCCCUCGCUUGGGCCCUUCUCUAUGCCUUAGUCUCUCCAGCACAUGCACACAGCAUGCACACACACGCACCCUACCCAAAGACAGCUGUGGCCCUCUCCCACCACCUCCCCCUUCCCACCGCUGGUUGUUGGGGGCUGGAGGCGGGAGGUCCCAUGGAAUUUGUUCUGGUUUCUAGGAUGUAAACGAGGACUCCAAGCCAUGAAUUGCCCUGCUUUCUAGAGGGUGGAAUGUUGACCCUGCAACUUUAGAAGCACAAUCAUUUAUUAAUAAUUUUUUUGAAACUCCCAUCUACCCCUGUUAGAGAAAUCAACAGGUUCUAGGAAUUAAAUAUGUCUCUUUGUAACCCAGAGCAUGUUCAAUUUUUGGAAACCGUAUUUCAGUGAUUUUCUUAAUACCUUACAUGUGUAGGGCAUCUUCCCCCAGAAUCUUACAGUCCCUUUCUGUGAAGAGAAGUGGACACACGUGGGAACUCUCACCAUCUCUGGACUGUCGUCAGGAAACGCCUGCAGGUCCUUGCCCUGUCUGUAUGGUGUCCUCACUUCUCCAUCCAUACAGGUGGCUCCAGUGGGCAUUUUUUUAUUUUAAAUUUUUUACAUGAAGCAAUAGAAGUACAAAAUACUUAUUUUUUCAAAAUUUAAUGUGUUCCAUGAAACCUGUUGGCAGUCGCUUUCCUUCCCCCACAUCUAAAUUCUUUGGUUUUUAGUUGUUUGUUUUUUGGAUUUUUUUUUUUUUUUUUUUGGCCUUGUAUCCCAAGGACUAAAAGAUUAGCACAGACACGUUUUGAUGUUGAAUGAACUAGUAAGUCACAGUAGGUGGUAGUCUUCAUUGAUUUCUCUGUAAGUUUUUAAAGAAUGUAUGAAGAUAGUCACGAAUGUACUGAGUGUUCGCAUCCCCCUUCAGUUCACCUUGGCUGUGUCUACAGGACAACAAAUGUUUGACAGGGAAUAAAGUCGUGUCUGGUGUCAUUUGCGCUAGCGUGCCCCUCCCCUUUCGGUGUUGGCUCCAAACCUUCCUUUCCUUUUAUGUUUGUGGGGAGUGGGGAACCACAUCAGCAGCAAUCAUCAACCAACCAACCAAUGGGAUCUACUUAGUGGUGAAUAGAUUGGCUAUUUAAUUGGUAAAAGUUGCUGGUCUGACCACACCACAGCAUGACCACUGGGUUCAUUUAGAGAUGGCCUCCGUUUCCAACGUUCCCCACAAAUGUUUGCUUCUUUCCCAGUCAAGAGGGGAUCUCGAGACUCCCGAGUGGAGGUCGUGAGCUUGCACCCCGCCUGGCUGUGUAGAUCGACUGUAUAGAUACAUGAAGUGGGGGUGAGGGCCAAGGGGCUAUUACUGCUGUUGGGAAAUACUUGCCUCUCGUAGAUCCAGCCUUAAUGUUUUUCUGACAUCCUAGUAAUAGCAGACCCUGCACAAAGUGGAUAUCAGACUUAAUACUGUGAGGAGACAAAAUAAUGAGAAUAGUUUUACCAAAGAUAAUGAAAUCUCGCAUCAUGUCUGCAUUUUACCAUAGAUUGGAGUGCAUCCUUAGGAAACUGAAUGUAACAAAAACCCAGGACAUUUUUGGAAAUUGUAUGCUCUCUAGCAACUUUGUGUGAAUUUUUAUACAAACACUGUUUUAUGAGUUAUAUAAAAUGUUAUAAAAAUAGAAAAA